CCGCGAAACUCGGCGGCUGAGCGUGGAGGUUCUUGUCUCCCCUGGUUUGUGAAGUGCGGAAAACCAGAGGCGCAGUCAUGUCGGGAUUCGACGAUCCUGGCAUUUUCUACAGCGACAGCUUCGGGGGCGACGCCCAGGCCGACGAGGGGCAGGCCCGCAAAUCGCAGCUGCAGAGGCGCUUCAAGGAGUUCCUGCGGCAGUACCGAGUGGGCACCGACCGCACGGGCUUCACCUUCAAAUACAGGGAUGAACUCAAGCGGCAUUACAACCUGGGGGAGUACUGGAUUGAGGUGGAGAUGGAGGAUCUGGCCAGCUUUGAUGAGGACCUGGCCGACUACUUGUACAAGCAGCCAGCCGAGCACCUGCAGCUGCUGGAGGAAGCUGCCAAGGAGGUAGCUGAUGAGGUGACCCGGCCCCGGCCUUCUGGGGAGGAGGUGCUCCAGGACAUCCAGGUCAUGCUCAAGUCGGACGCCAGCCCUUCCAGCAUUCGUAGCCUGAAGUCGGACAUGAUGUCACACCUGGUGAAGAUCCCUGGCAUCAUCAUCGCGGCCUCUGCGGUCCGUGCCAAGGCCACCCGCAUCUCUAUCCAGUGCCGCAGCUGCCGCAACACCCUCACCAACAUUGCCAUGCGCCCUGGCCUCGAGGGCUAUGCCCUGCCCAGGAAGUGCAACACAGAUCAGGCUGGGCGCCCCAAAUGCCCAUUGGACCCGUACUUCAUCAUGCCCGACAAAUGCAAAUGCGUGGACUUCCAGACCCUGAAGCUGCAGGAGCUGCCUGAUGCAGUCCCCCACGGGGAGAUGCCCAGACACAUGCAGCUCUACUGCGACAGGUACCUGUGUGACAAGGUCGUCCCUGGGAACAGGGUUACCAUCAUGGGCAUCUACUCCAUCAAGAAGUUUGGCCUGACUACCAGCAGGGGCCGUGACAGGGUGGGCGUGGGCAUCCGAAGCUCCUACAUCCGUGUCCUGGGCAUCCAGGUGGACACAGAUGGCUCUGGCCGCAGCUUUGCUGGGGCCGUGAGCCCCCAGGAGGAGGAGGAGUUCCGUCGCCUGGCUGCCCUCCCAAAUGUCUAUGAGGUCAUCUCCAAGAGCAUCGCCCCCUCCAUCUUUGGGGGCACAGACAUGAAGAAGGCCAUUGCCUGCCUGCUCUUUGGGGGCUCCCGAAAGAGGCUCCCUGAUGGACUUACUCGCCGAGGAGACAUCAACCUGCUGAUGCUAGGGGACCCUGGGACAGCCAAGUCCCAGCUUCUGAAGUUUGUGGAGAAGUGUUCUCCCAUUGGGGUAUACACGUCUGGGAAAGGCAGCAGCGCAGCUGGACUGACAGCCUCGGUGAUGAGGGACCCUUCGUCCCGGAAUUUCAUCAUGGAGGGCGGAGCCAUGGUCCUGGCCGAUGGUGGGGUCGUCUGUAUUGACGAGUUUGACAAGAUGCGAGAAGAUGACCGUGUGGCAAUCCACGAAGCCAUGGAGCAGCAGACCAUCUCUAUCGCCAAGGCUGGGAUCACCACCACCCUGAACUCCCGCUGCUCCGUCCUGGCUGCUGCCAACUCAGUGUUCGGCCGCUGGGAUGAGACGAAGGGGGAGGACAACAUUGACUUCAUGCCCACCAUCUUGUCGCGCUUCGACAUGAUCUUCAUCGUCAAGGAUGAGCACAAUGAGGAGAGGGAUGUGAUGCUGGCCAAGCAUGUCAUCACUCUGCACGUGAGCGCACUGACACAGACACAGGCUGUGGAGGGCGAGAUUGACCUGGCCAAGCUGAAGAAGUUUAUUGCCUACUGCCGAGUGAAGUGUGGCCCCCGGCUGUCAGCAGAGGCUGCAGAGAAACUGAAGAACCGCUACAUCAUCAUGCGGAGCGGGGCCCGUCAGCACGAGAGGGACAGUGACCGCCGCUCCAGCAUCCCCAUCACUGUGCGGCAGCUGGAGGCCAUUGUGCGCAUCGCGGAAGCCCUCAGCAAGAUGAAGCUGCAGCCCUUCGCCACAGAGGCAGAUGUGGAGGAGGCCCUGCGGCUCUUCCAAGUGUCCACGUUGGAUGCUGCCUUGUCCGGUACCCUGUCAGGGGUGGAGGGCUUCACCAGCCAGGAGGACCAGGAGAUGCUGAGCCGCAUCGAGAAGCAGCUCAAGCGCCGCUUUGCCAUUGGCUCCCAGGUGUCUGAGCACAGCAUCAUCAAGGACUUCACCAAGCAGAAAUACCCGGAGCACGCCAUCCACAAGGUGCUGCAGCUCAUGCUGCGGCGCGGCGAGAUCCAGCAUCGCAUGCAGCGCAAGGUUCUCUACCGCCUCAAGUGAGUCGCGCCGCCUCACUGGACUCAUGGACUCGCCCACGCCUCGCCCCUCCUGCCGCUGCCUGCCAUUGACAAUGUUGCUGGGACCUCUGCCUCCCCACUGCAGCCCUCGAACUUCCCAGGCACCCUCCUUUCUGCCCCAGAGGAAGGAGCUGUAGUGUCCUGCUGCCUCUGGGCGCCCGCCUCUAGCGCGGUUCUGGGAAGUGUGCUUUUGGCAUCCGUUAAUAAUAAAGCCACGGUGUGUUCAGGUAUCUGUGGGUUUGUGCACUCGGUGACCUGUCACCUCCAUCGUGCCCUCAUGGCAGGGUAAGUGUGAGGGAACAGGGUCUGGAGGCAGACUGGCCAGGGUUUCUGACUUGGAUCUGCCACUCAGACUUCUGGGUAAGUCACGUGACUUGAGUGCUCCGGUUUCUUCAUCUGUUUAGCGGGGCUCAUAAAGCCACUCCCUUGAUGCUGGGAAUCCAGUGAGACCAGGGAGUGGGGAAGCGCUUCUCAAAGUGUGUGAUUUUGAUCCGCCUCACCUGUUCCCCAGUAACUUAUUGGGGGGCUGCGAGCCGUGGUGCGGCGGUCAGACUGCCUGGAUUCAUGGACCCUCUCCAUGCCUUAGUUUCCUUAUCUGUAAGCAGGCUGAUACUAGAACCUGCUUCACAGGGUUGUGCUUAGGGUCAGUGAGCAGCUGUUAGUGAGGGGAAUGUAGUGGCCACCAGGCAGGAACUAGGACUCCAGCCAGUUCUUUCCUGGUGGGCCACGUGUAACUGUGUGGCCUUGGGCGAGACAUUUCACUUUUCUGUGCCUGAGUUUAUCAGUAAACUGGAGAUGGGGGGAUUCCUCACCCUGAGUUGUGAGGAUUGAAUGACAGAAGGCACUAGUGACAGUGAUGCUGGAGGAAGGAGUGUUGCCAAGUGCCUCGGUCACUUUGCCUAAUUUCAGAAAGUCACUCUGAGUUGGUAUGUUUUGUGUUUUUAAAAAAGCUAGGAUUCAUAAAAUUAAAUAGAAAUCAGUGAAAUAAAAUAUUUGAUAUUUAAAAUACAUUUAGAAAUACAAAGUGUCAAGCAAAACGUGAAUUUGGAAAUCUAUGGAACAUUAGAUAAGGUAUUUAAAAGUAAUUGCCAUGUAAAAAUGACACGAACUUGAAGUAAGAUUAUUUGAUUUUUCUAAAAAUACAAGAAAGCUUGGUGCA